AGCCGGUGAAUGAAUUCCUCUCUGCUGGGCGGCCUUGCCGACGCACUUUUCUCAGCAAGAAUUCCCGAAACCGCAGCAGGAGGGAGUCCAGGAGCCAAGGUUGCCGCGGUGUCUCCGUCAGCCUCACCAUGAACCUGGAACCGCCCAAGGCUGAGUUCCGGUCAGCCACCAGGGUGGCCGGGGGACCUGUCACCCCCAGGAAAGGGCCCCCUAAAUUUAAGCAGCGACAGACCAGGCAGUUCAAGAGCAAGCCCCCAAAGAAAGGCGUUCAAGGGUUUGGGGACGACAUCCCUGGAAUGGAAGGCCUGGGAACAGACAUCACAGUCAUCUGCCCUUGGGAGGCCUUCAACCACCUGGAGCUGCACGAGCUGGCCCAAUAUGGCAUCAUCUAGCACGAGGCCCUGCUGAAGUCCAGACCCUCCCCCUCCUGCCCACUGUGCUCUAAACCCUGCUCAGGAUUCCUGUUGAGGAGAUGCCUCCCUAGCCCAGAUGGCACCUGGACACCAGGAUGGGACUGCAACCUCAGGUCUCCCCCUACAUAUUAAUACCAGUCACCAGGAGCCCACCACCUCCCUCUAGGAUGCCCCCUCAGGGGCUGGCCAGGCCCUGCUCAACAUCUGGAGAUACAGGCCCACCCCUCAGUCCUGCCCACAGAGAGGCUUGGUCGGUCUCCACUCCCAGGGAGAACGGGAAGUGGACCCCAGCCCGGGAGCCUGCUGGACCCCAGAUCGUCCCCUCCUCCCAGCUGGAAAGCUAGGGCAGGUCUCCCCAGAGUGCUUCUGCACCCCAGCCCCCUGUCCUGCCUGUAAGGGGAUACAGAGAAGCUCCCCGUCUCUGCAUCCCUUCCCAGGGGGGUGCCCUUAGUUUGGACAUGCUGGGUAGCAGGACUCCAGGGCGUGCACGGUGAGCAGAUGAGGCCCCAAGCUCAUCACACCAGGGGGCCAUCCUUCUCAAUACAGCCUGCCCUUGCAGUCCCUAUUUCAAAAUAAAAUUAGUGUGUCCUUGCC